CCAGGUUCAAGCGAUUCUCCUGCCUCAGCCUCCCGAGUAGCUGGGACUAGCACGCGCCGCCAUGCCCGGCUAAUUUUUGUAUUAUUAGUAUUUUGUAUUAUUAGUAGAGACAGGGUUUCACCAUGUUGGCCAGGAUGGUCUCCAUCUUGGCCUCCCGAAGUGCUGGAAUUACAGGUGUGAGCCACUGCACCCGGCCUAAAAUUUGUUUCAAUGCAUCAAUAACAAUGGUGUUUACUAAAAUAUUAGUGUGGAAAAGGUUUUAUGGUGUAUUAUUUUUGCUUUUCAUAUCUCCAGGCUACUUAAUUGAAGGUUUUAUUGAAAUAAGUGUAGACUCACAAGCAGUCAUAAGAAAUAAUACAGAAAAAGCCCUGUCCAUAUUACCCAGGGUUCCGUCAUGAUUACAUUUUGCAAACUAUAGUAUAAUAUCACUCUAAUGAUAUUGACUCUUCUGUGUUCUGUUUUUAUAUAUUUCCCUAGUUUUGCUUGUAUUUACUUGUUGCAUGUGUGUAAGCCCUGAGUUUUAUAGGUUUGAUUUGUGGAUCUGUUGUGCGGUUGAGCCCUCAUUCAUUCACCUGCUUCUCUGCAGUUGGACACACAAGCAAUUGCCUUUGCACGAACAGGGACAAUCUUAAUUUCUGUUUAAGAUGAGAAAAUAUGGUUGGAGACACAUUAAAACUUCUGUCUCCACUGAUGACAAGAUACUUCUUUCUGCUUUUUUAUUCUACUGAUUCUUCAGACCUCAAUGAAAAUCAACAUCCCCUAGAUUUUGAUGAAAUGGCUUUUGGAAAAGUAAAAUCAGGGAUUAGCUUCCUCAUUCAGACUGGAGUUGGGAUCCUGGGAAAUUCCUUUCUCCUUUGUUUUUAUAACUUAAUUUUGUUCACUGGACACAAGCUGAGACCCACGGACUUGAUUCUCAGCCAACUGGCCUUGGCUAACUCCAUGGUCCUUUUCUUUAAAGGGAUACCUCAGACAAUGGCAGCUUUUGGAUUGAAAUAUUUGCUGAAUGACACUGGAUGUAAGUUUGUCUUUUAUUAUCACAGGGUGGGCACAAGAGUUUCCCUCAGCACCAUCUGCCUUCUCAAUGGAUUCCAAGCCAUUAAGCUCAACCCCAGUAUAUGCAGGUGGAUGGAGAUCAAGAUUAGAUCCCCAAGGUUUAUUGACUUCUGUUGUCUCCUCUGCUGGGCCCCCCAUGUCUUGAUGAAUGCAUCUGUUCUUCUAUUAGUGAAUGGCCCACUGAAUAGCAAAAACAGUAGUGCAAAAAACAAUUAUGGAUACUGUUCUUACAAAGCAUCAAAGAGAUUUAGCUCAUUACAUGCAGUCUUAUAUUUUUCCCCUGAUUUUAUGAGUUUGGGCUUCAUGGUCUGGGCCAGUGGCUCCAUGGUCUUCUUCCUCUACAGACACAAGCAGCAAGUCCAACACAAUCACAGCAACAGACUCUCCUGCAGACCUUCCCAGGAAGCCAGAGCCACACACACCAUCAUGGUCCUGGUGAGCUCCUUUUUUGUUUUCUAUUCAGUCCAUAGUUUUCUGACAAUUUGGACAACUGUAGUUGCAAACCCAGGCCAGUGGAUAGUGACCAACUCUGUGUUGGUCGCCUCAUGUUUCCCAGCACGCAGCCCUUUUGUCCUCAUCAUGAGUGAUACUCAUAUCUCUCAGUUCUGUUUUGCCUGCAGGACAAGGAAAACACUCUUUCCUAAUCUGGUUGUCAUGCCAUGAGUCUUUUCUCUUCAUGGAAUUCAGCUAUUUAUCAUAACUCUUGCUAAGAUUUAGGAAAUAUUAACUACUAGUUAUUUGUGAUAGCAACAUACACAUGGCCAGUAAUGCUCUUGUCCAGGAAGAUCUAAUACCAGAGCUAAAAAUGAAAGUCAUGGAUACUGUUACACAAAGAACACUCUAUAUAACUGUGUUAAGUCCUUCAGACAAGUUCAGGAAAUCAAAAAGUUUAAAAAGGGAAUUCUUUAGAGAUUUAGGGGAGAUUUCUCAUUUUUGUACUAUGAAGAAUCAUGGAAUGUUUUAAAAAUAUUUUUAAAGCACAGUUUGAUUCAGGUGCUUCUUGAACAGCAUAAAUCCCCUGGAGAGUCCACAUGUAAGAAAGACAUGUGCAGGCCGGGCACAGUGGCUCACGCCUGUAAUCCCACCGUUUUGGGAGGCUGAGGCACUCCCAAAUGCCUCAAGUGAUCCACUCAAGAUGACUUGAGGCCAGGAGUUCGAGACCAGCCUGGCCAACAUGGCAAAAACCCUGUCUCAAAUACAAAAAUUAGCCAACCAUGUGGCACACACCUGUAGUCCCAGCUACUCCAGAGGGUGAAGCACGAGAAUUACUUACCAGCUUGGGUGACGGAGGGAGACUC